CCCCGCUUCCAGUCAGAGUUCAAGUUAAAACAGAAAAAAGGAAGAUGGCAAGAAUAUUGUUACUUUUCCUCCCGGGUCUUGUGGCUGUAUGUGCUGUGCAUGGAAUAUUUAUGGACCGUCUAGCUUCCAAGAAGCUCUGUGCAGAUGAUGAGUGUGUCUAUACUAUUUCUCUGGCUAGUGCUCAAGAAGAUUAUAAUGCCCCGGACUGUAGAUUCAUUAACGUUAAAAAAGGGCAGCAGAUCUAUGUGUACUCAAAGCUGGUAAAAGAAAAUGGAGCUGGAGAAUUUUGGGCUGGCAGUGUUUAUGGUGAUGGCCAGGACGAGAUGGGAGUCGUGGGUUAUUUCCCCAGGAACUUGGUCAAGGAACAGCGUGUGUACCAGGAAGCUACCAAGGAAGUUCCCACCACGGAUAUUGACUUCUUCUGCGAGUAAUAAAUUAGUUAAAACUGCAAAUAGAAAGAAAACACCAAAAAUAAAGAAAAGAGCAAAAGUGGCCAAAAAAUGCAUGUCUGUAAUUUUGGACUGACGUUUUAAGAAUUUGUUACCUUACAGAAGAGCAAGGGCUUAGGGGUUGGAGGUGGCAGAUAAAAGAGGAUUUUCAACUCAAAUCUUGUUUCCUGCUGGCCUGGUCUGCCCACGAGCUAGAGCGGGGAAAUGUUGAGCUCAAAUGGGUAAAUUGAGACCAGAAAAUUAUUUUUUCAACCUAGAGAAUCUCCUCUUACAGGGGGAUGCAUAUAACAGAUCAUGUAUGUGUAGUUAUUUCUAAGUAGUAAUUCUUCCCAGCUCUUUGAUUUGCCAUAUAUAAAAUAGGUGGGUCGUAUGUCUUCCCUUUAGACAUGAUGUUUUCUACUCAUUUGUCUCUCUGGCCAAUUGAAUUAUUAAUAAAAGGUCUGUAUUAUCAAAGAGUAUUCUAGUAUUUUUGUUACUUUUAAUAUUUGAUGCCUUUUGGAGGUAAAGCUGUUGGGGGAAGAAGAGUUUUUGGACCCAUAGAUGUUUGGAUGAUGUCUCUAAUUUGUCAUUUAGAAAAAUCUCAAAAAUGAUUUCAGUUGAAUAACUUGCCUUCUAAAUGAUCAAUUUACUUCUCCCCCAAUUUUAAAGAAGUAUGUGUAUAUUUAAUAGGGGAAGGUAGUUUAUGGAAAUAUUUUUAAUGGAAUAGUUUUCCCUUAAUAUGUAUCCUUGCUGGAUAUUAUUCAAGCUGCAAGUCAUCAAAAGACCCAGAAAAAAAAAAGUCUGUAGGUUAUUUUCUCUACUUCUAUUUCAACUUUGAAUUUCCUCUUCCUGUGCAAAUUCCUCUAGUCAAGUGUGAUAUAUCAAGAAAUCUGAGGAGGAUGCAGGUUUUGUGGUCCUGAUGGGCCCACAAGUUUUUCUAUAUUUAACUGGAAAUAUGCUUUGAUUUUGUGUUAUUAAUAUAAUUCUUUUGAUGUAGUCAUGAGUUUUUCUUUGUUUGCAUAUAAUUAAAAUGCCUCUACUUAAUGUCA